GGAGCCCCAGCCGCUAGUGCUGGUGGCCGCCGCUGCUGCCCCAGCUGGAGCCCGAGCCGCCGCCUCUGCGUCCGCGCGUCGCUGCUUCCCAGGGCGGCGGUAUGCUGGGGAAAGGAGUAGUCGGCGGUGGCGGCGGCACCAAGGCCCCCAAGCCCUCCUUCGUGUCGUACGUACGCCCUGAGGAAAUUCACACAAACGAAAAGGAAGUAACAGAGAAGGAAGUAACUCUUCACUUGUUGCCAGGUGAACAGCUGCUUUGUGAAGCCAGCACAGUACUGAAGUAUGUCCAGGAAGAUUCCUGUCAGCAUGGGGUCUAUGGGAGGCUUGUCUGCACAGACUUCAAGAUUGCCUUCUUGGGUGAUGAUGAAUCUGCAUUGGAUAAUGAUGAAACUCAAUUUAAGAAUAAGGUUAUAGGAGAAAAUGACAUUACACUCCACUGUGUUGAUCAGAUUUAUGGAGUGUUUGAUGAGAAAAAGAAAACUCUCUUUGGACAACUGAAGAAAUACCCUGAGAAGCUCAUCAUCCACUGCAAAGACCUUCGAGUGUUCCAGUUUUGUCUGAGGUACACAAAGGAAGAGGAAGUCAAAAGGAUUGUCAGUGGCAUAAUUCAUCAUACCCAGGCUCCUAAACUGCUUAAACGAUUAUUUCUGUUUUCCUAUGCGACUGCUGCACAAAACAAUACAGUCACUGAUCCCAAGAACCAUACCGUAAUGUUUGACACACUUAAGGACUGGUGUUGGGAACUGGAACGGACCAAAGGCAACAUGAAGUACAAAGCAGUGAGUGUCAACGAAGGCUAUAAAGUCUGUGAGAGAUUGCCAGCAUACUUUGUUGUCCCCACCCCUCUUCCUGAAGAGAAUGUGCAGCGCUUUCAGGGUCAUGGCAUACCAAUAUGGUGUUGGUCCUGCCACAAUGGAAGUGCCCUUUUGAAAAUGUCAGCACUGCCCAAAGAACAGGAUGACGGCAUUUUACAAAUCCAAAAGAGCUUCUUAGAUGGAAUUUACAAGACCAUCCACAGGCCACCCUAUGAAAUUGUUAAAACGGAAGACCUGUCAAGCAACUUCCUGUCCCUGCAGGAAAUCCAGACUGCAUACUCUAAAUUUAAACAGCUAUUUCUGAUAGAUAACAGUACUGAAUUUUGGGACACAGAUAUAAAAUGGUUUUCUCUGUUGGAAAGUAGCAGCUGGCUUGACAUAAUCAGACGUUGCCUGAAAAAAGCAAUAGAGAUUACAGAAUGUAUGGAAGCACAAAACAUGAAUGUUCUUCUUUUAGAGGAGAAUGCAUCCGACCUCUGCUGUCUCAUUUCCUCUCUGGUGCAACUGAUGAUGGACCCCCACUGCAGAACCAGAAUUGGUUUCCAGAGCCUCAUCCAAAAGGAGUGGGUCAUGGGUGGCCACUGUUUCUUGGAUCGCUGCAACCAUCUCCGCCAGAACGACAAAGAGGAGGUUCCUGUGUUCCUGCUUUUCCUAGAUUGUGUCUGGCAGCUGGUGCACCAGCAUCCCCCGGCAUUUGAAUUCACAGAGACUUACCUGACUGUUUUGUCAGAUAGCCUGUAUAUACCUAUUUUUAGCACCUUCUUCUUCAAUUCACCUCAUCAAAAAGAUACUAACAUGGGUAGAGAAGGCCAGGAUACACAAAGCAAGCCUUUGAAUCUGCUCACCGUGUGGGAUUGGUCGGUGCAGUUUGAACCCAAAGCCCAGACAUUGCUCAAAAACCCUCUUUAUGUGGAAAAGCCAAAACUGGACAAAGGCCAACGGAAAGGAAUGCGCUUCAAACAUCAACGACAACUUUCUUUGCCACUUACACAAUCUAAGUCAUCUCCCAAAAGAGGAUUUUUCAGGGAAGAAACAGAUCAUUUAAUUAAAAACCUUCUGGGCAAGAGAAUUAGCAAACUUAUUAAUUCUUCUGAUGAGCUCCAAGACAACUUUCGAGAGUUCUAUGACAGCUGGCAUAGCAAGUCCACUGACUACCAUGGUUUGUUGUUACCGCAUAUCGAGGGGCCCGAAAUCAAAGUCUGGGCCCAGCGCUACCUACGUUGGAUUCCAGAAGCCCAAAUCCUAGGUGGUGGCCAAGUGGCCACUCUGAGCAAACUCUUGGAAAUGAUGGAGGAAGUCCAGAGUUUACAAGAGAAGAUCGACGAGAGACACCACAGCCAGCAGGCCCCCCAGGCUGAGGCCCCCUGCCUGCUGAGGAACUCUGCCCGCCUCUCGUCUUUGUUUCCUUUCGCUCUGCUCCAGCGACAUUCCUCUAAGCCCGUCUUACCCACCAGUGGCUGGAAAGCUUUGGGAGAUGAAGACGAUUUGGCCAAACGAGAAGAUGAGUUCGUGGACCUAGGGGAUGUGUGACCUGUUUGUUGAGUGAUUGUGAAAGAGGAAUGUGGGAGAUUGGGACAGCUGAUCCCUGGAUUUGUGUCACGCUACAGCUCAUGCUGGCUGGGUCCUUAGCCCGGCACUCCGUUAGAAUAAACCUGGGCCUUCGGGAAAAGAGGUGGCUCUCAUUAUUUUUCAUGAUUCUAAAAGACUAUGCAAUUAAAACCGCAUCUGUAGUAUUACUAAUUGGAAGGAAUUAUUACUUGACCCGUAAUAGGGUUGUGGCCGUUUUCUGAUGCCUAAGUAUUAUACAGAGCCCACAAUGGCCAGUUUACUACCAGAAAGGGCUUCAGUAAGAUAUUCUUGGACUUGAUACUUUCUUCAGAUCCUCUUUGUGCCAAGAUAAUUUAUCCAGUCAUUGGGAAUAGUAAGUUUCUGUGUAACCCAUCUCAAUUAUAGAAGCAAGUUCAGCUUUAUGUAUUUGUAUGGGGAGUUGAAGAUUCAGAUAGAGGUAUUAAGAUGUGUGGCAUUUACUUAAACCAUCACAUUUUUUUCUUUCUACGCCCCCUUGCCUGUAAAACACCUGGGAAGUUCCACUGGUGUCAUCCAUCCUGAUGCUUCAGACCACCCUCCCUUCUUCACAGACCGUGUCACUUUGCCUGUGGGUGGGGGCUAGCCAGCCACCACCCUCUUUUCUGUGCUGCCAGCCCCAGGUCUUCCUCCGCCUGCUCCACACCACUCGCCGCUGUCCCUCUGCACUCCCUGCCUUGGUGCGUGUAGUCCCAGUGUCUCACUGCCAAACCUCUUGGUUACGCUGCGGGGAUCUGUUUCUUUGCCUGAGAUCCUUCCUGAGGAGCGUCCAUUCCUCUGGAGUCUCUCCUUGUUUGGAACAAAUCGCUUCGCCUUUUUCUACUUGCCUGCUGAAGCUUUGGAGCACUUGUGAUUGCAGUUUUCUGCCGCAACCCCUGAGCCGAGUUCCUCACAUUCUUUUACCUUUAUGGACUGAUGGGAUUGGGUCACUUUUGAAUGUGGCUUUCAUAGGAAAGCAGCUUAAACAUAAAUAUCAGAAGUGAUGAUUAUCAUAUGAUACCUCAGUGAUUUUAAAAGCCAUAGAAGAAACUUGACUAUGCCUGGUCACCUUCUUGGAUCUGCUGUCUAAAUGAUAUAUAUAUGAUAUAUAUGUGAUAUAUAUAUAUCAUAUAUAUGAUAUAUAUAUAUAUAUCACAUAUAUAUGAUAUAUAUAUGAUAUAUAUAUAUCACAUAUAUAUGAUAUAUAUAUCAUAUAUAUGAUAUAUAUUUUUUUUAAUGCAGGAAAGUAUACUUUGUAAGGAGCAGAUUUUUUUGUUCUCAGUGGAACCCUGUCAAAUCGCAUAAAAGAGGAAAAAAACAAAACUCAUUAGAAUGUUUUAAAUUGAAUGUUCGCCUUUUACAUAUAUUUGCUCUUCAGUAUGGAUCCCAAUUUGAAUGUUACAUGUUCGGAAAAACUUUCAGUUGCUCAAGGGCAAUAAGAAAAUUUGAGGCCGGGUGUGGUGGCUCACGCCUGUAAUCCCAGCACUUUGGGAGGCUCAGGUGGGCGAAUUGCUUGAGCCCAGGAGUUCGAGACCAGCCGGGGCAACAUGGCAAAACCCUGUCUCUACUAAAAAUACAAAAAUUAGCUGGGUGUGGUGGUGCAUGCCUGUAGUCCCAGCUACUCGGGAGGCUGAGGUGGGAGGAUCCCGUGAGCCUGGGAGGUGGAGUUUGCAGUGAGCUAAGAUCGUGCCACUGCACUCCGGCCUGGGUGAUGGAGCAAGACCUCGUCUCAGAAAAUUGGAAACUAUUGACUAAGAGAAGUUUCUAGGUUUGCACUGAAUUGUCUUUUGUACAUACAGUGAAUUGUUUUGCUGUUCUCCCCACUCCAUAUUAAUGCAGGAGCCAGGUUGGUCUGUUAGGAUGAACAAAGGUUGAGGGGAGGGCAGGAUUCGUGCAUCUGGGGGCCAAACACAUGUUCCGUCUUGAUUGCCUUAAGAGUUACUAGCGAGGUCAGUGUUAGGCUUGCAAUAGGGAUUUUAAAAUACACUAACUAGUUCCUUAGCUACCUUCACAUACAUUCUAUAGGCCUUCUUAAAUUAGCACUAACCUCCACUUCCUUCUCUGCCCCAUUGCCUCCCAAAUAUGCUAUGGAGCUAUUUUUGUUACCACGUUAUAACGUGAAUAUUUAUACAGUAGCCUCUUCAGGCUUUGUAAUUUUCAUUCCAAAAAUGCCCGGUGUGAUGCUUUACACUCUACAAAGUAUGGUUUAAAGGCACAAGGUCAUGGCCUUUGUCAUAGCAGUUGAAUGUGCAUUGACAUAUUUUUCUAUGAUUUUUUAAAAUUACAAUAGAAAAAUAAGCUGUUGUAACGUGUAAGGUCAUGACAAUUUUUGUAUUUAUAUUUGAAAUCAGAUUUCUAUAACUCGUAUUUGUGUACAGAAUUCUCAAUGGAUUUAUAUAUUGUGAAAUUUUUAUCUGAGAUUGGGAUGUGGAUUAUGCUUAACAGUGAGAGCUGAAAUGAGACCAUUUACUUUGUUUAAAAUGCUGUACUGUGCAAGUUUGGAAAUGUAAAUUAAUUUACUGUAUAUAAUAUCUUGAGUUUGUUUAUACCUCCAAGUUUUUACACUGAAGAUAAACUAGCUUUAAUUCAAAACUUUUUUUUUCUUUAUAAGGGAAUAAGCUGUUGAGCUAAACCUGUAUACUUGUGCUUUUUAUUUUCUGGAUGCACAAUGAAAGUUUAUACUUGUAUCUCACUGCAUCAUAUCUGAUUGCAGAAAUUAAAGCACAAUUUACAAGCAA